GGAUUACAGGCGAGAGCCACUGCUGUUGGCCAGGACUGAGGGGUAACAUUACCUGUAAUGUUGCCGUCUCCCUCUAAACUUGGGGCCAACAAUUUUCUUUACACCCAAAUGUUUGAGACACUAACUGCUCCUUGUUAAGGAGAAUUGUACUAAUUACAAUUAGUAAUUGCUCGGUUGCUAAAAUGAGGGUCACAGCAGCCUUACUCCUAAAAUUAUCUUCACAGGUAGGCAAGAUGGCAAGGUCAAAGAAGGUAGUCUCAGGUGGUGUUUAUAGUUGUCCAGUGCUUACUUUGAAAAGGUGUUUUAGCUUCAAACUGCUCAUAAUUGGCAUAUAACCGGCGAUUUGUAGCAGAGUGAGAGAAUUAAGUGUUAAAGACAAAUAACUAUAUACUAUCUAUUUUCCUCAGAAUCCUCUUAAUAAACUUUAAAAAAUCACGUCAUUCUGCAACUUUUUUUUUUUUUUUUUGGAGAUGAAGUUUCGCUAGUCGCCCAGGCAAUGGUGCAAUCUCGGCUCACUGGAAUCUCCGCCUCCCAGGUUCAAGUGAUUCUCCUGCCUCAGCCUCCCAAGUAGCUAGGAUUAUAGGCGUGUACCACUACACCUGGCUAAUUUUUGUAUUUUUAGUAGGGACUUGGUUUCACCAUGCUGGCCAGGCUGGUCUUGACCUCCUUACGUCAGGUGAUCCGCCUGCCUUGGCCUCCCAAAGUGCUGGGAUUGCAGGCAUGAGCCACUGUGCCCGGCCUGCAACAUGAUAAUUUAAGGGGAAAAAUAUAUAUAUUUUUCUCCCAAAGUGUUGAGAUUACAGGCAUGAGCCACCACGCCCAGGGAUUUUUUUUGUUUGUUUUUUUUGAGACUGAGUCUUGCUCUGUUGCUUAGGCUGGAGUGCAGUGGCGUGAUCUCAGCUCACUGCAACCUCUGCCUCCUGGGUUCAAGCAAUUCUCAUGCCUCAGCUUCCCAAGUCGCUGGCAUUACAGGAGUGUGCCACCACACCUGGCUAAUUUUUGUAUUUUUUUAGUAGAGAUGUGGUUUCACUAUGCUGGCCAGGCUGGUCUCAAACCCCGGACCUCAGGUGAUCCACCCGCCUCGGCCUCCCAAAGUGCUGGGAUUACACGCAUGAGUCACUGUGCCUGGCCUGCGACAUGAUAAUUUAAGGAAAAAAAAAAUUAUUUCAUUCCUUCAGCUUUUGAGUGCUUGCUAUGUGGCAAGCACUGUAUUUAAAAUUGGGAAAACAAAUGAAAAUAAGAUAAACCUUGCUGUUUCUUGGUGGGUACACAGCCUACUUCCUGGGGAGACUGACAGAUGAUCUCUAGUAUGUUCAGCACCGUGUGUGUGCUGGGGGAUAGUGGUACAGGGUGCCGUAAGAGCAUGUUGGCUGGCCUAAGAACCUAGACUUGGUUAGACAAGCCUUUGGGCAGGAACGGACUUCUGAAUCUAGACCGGAAGUAGUUAGUAAAGAUGGUAGGGAGAGUCUUUCAGUCAAAACACAGUGUACACAUCUUAAACUUUCUUACCUGAACGUCAGAGUGACCUGAAACAUUCAGUUCUUUGAAGUGGAAUGAAGCAAAAUAAAUUUCUUAGUGACACAUUUUUUGACUUCUUCCACUGAAGGGGUAUGAACUUUAGAAAGUUUCAUAAUUAAGGGGAAAAGAAAGCAAUAUUGAAUUAUAUACUUGGCUAGGCACGGUGGCUCACACACUAUUAUCCCAGCACUGUGAGAGGUUGAGGUGGGAGGAUCAUGAGCUCAGGAAUUUGAGACCAGUCUGGACAACAUAGACCCCCCCAUCUCUACAAAAAUAAAAAAUAAAAAUAAUAAUUAUACACUCUACUUACGUUGUGCUGCGUAUCAGAGCUGUAACCAAAGCAAUUGAAUGCUGUUUUAAGUACUACUAUCCUUUGGGUAAGGGGUAAAAUGAGCCAGUGAGGCCUCUUUAAAACAGUAUUUGAGUUAACCAUUUUUCUAUGAACUUACGUUGCAUUGUUUUUAGAAAAAUACUUGGUGUCAGAAUAUGAACUGUAUUUAAUAUAGCAUAUGCUUUUUAAAAAAUAUUAUUCUCUAAGGCAAGUACUUUUAACUUUAUAUCCUAAAUAACUCUUUUUACUCUUGAACAUUGGCCGGUCCUUCUUUCAGGAUUCCCUGAAUCGUUUGACCGUAUCUUUAGAGAAGUGCUCAGUAAGUCGAGGGCUGAACCUGUCCAGUGAGUGGUGAGCAGAGCUUGAUUCUCCACCAACCCAUGGCUUAGCUCUGAGAAGACUGUUGAGUUGUGAUCUUAAUUUUCUUCUUUAAGCGAUGGUAGUGCUAUCUUCAAGGUUAGGCUUGAAUUUGAUUAAAGUAGAAUUUUAAGAACUUAGUCAAAUUAUAGUUGUUCCAGGAGGUCAGUUUCAUUCCUGUAAAAUUUUACUUUGUAACCCAAGCUGCACUGAAGCUCUCUUAGGUCAACUCUGCCUAAAGAGGCACCUGAUUAUUACUGUUAUUUUUUUUUUUAGGUUAAAUCAUUUCUUAUAUGAGCCAUCUUUAUGCUGCCUCCCUAAACCUCAUCACCCCAAAUUUGUCUUCAGAGGCACAGAUUUUUUUUUCUGCAAGACAGACCAGUAAUAUGCGUAAAUUCACAGAGAAACACGAAUGGGUAACAACAGAAAAUGGCAUUGGAACAGUGGGAAUCAGCAAUUUUGCACAGGAAGCGUUGGGAGAUGUUGUUUAUUGUAGUCUCCCUGAAGUUGGGACAAAAUUGAACAAACAAGAUGAGUUUGGUGCUUUGGAAAGUGUGAAAGCUGCUAGUGAACUCUAUUCUCCUUUAUCAGGAGAAGUAACUGAAAUUAAUGAAGCUCUUGCAGAAAAUCCAGGACUUGUAAACAAAUCUUGUUAUGAAGAUGGUUGGCUGAUCAAGAUGACACUGAGUAACCCUUCAGAACUAGAUGAACUUAUGAGUGAAGAAGCAUAUGAGAAAUACAUAAAAUCUAUUGAGGAGUGAAAAUGGAACUCCUAAAUAAACUAGUAUGAAAUAACGCAAGCCAGCAGAGUUGUCUUAAAUUAGUGGUGGAUAGAAGACUUAGAAUAGAAACUUUUAGUAUUACCGAUGGGGAAAAAAAAACUACUGUUAACACUGCUAAUGAAAGAAAAUGCCCUUUAACUUUCUAAUGAUUAUAGAUAAAUAUAAUAUGCGUCUUUUUCACAAUAUCCUAUGAUUUUUAGACUAGGCUCUAGUGUUCAGAAUUCAUGAAAUUAUCCAUGGUAAAAACUAGUUAUAAAAAUUACAUAAUUCAAAGAUAACAUUGUUAUUCUUAAGCCUUAUAUAAUAUUGUAACUUGCAUGUAUCCAUACCUGGAUUUGGGAUGAAAUACUUAAUGAUCUUUCCAUUGGAAAUAACUGGAAGUGAAGAGGUUUUGUUGCUUGUACAGUGUCAGAUGAGGAACACCACUAUCUUAAUUUUGCGAUACACUGCAUUUGCUGGUGCUAUUUUUAUACAGUGAAGCAACAGCUUUGCAGCAAAAUAAUAAAAUACUUCUUCGUUAAUCAUGUUUGUUUUGAUGUUAAUAUUUCAUUUAGUAACUCUGCUAGUAUUUGUGAAAGUGCUAACUUUAACUUACGGAAAGUUACUUUUUAAAAGGAAAUUUAAGCCAGAACAAUGCAAAGCUCCAAGAAAAUGUUUUCUUUAGUCACAAAUCUGGUUUUUCUUAAGCCAAGAUCUGUCACCUUUAACAUAAUAAAAAAUAAAUCACCAACUUUGAUUUUCUAUCAUGCGAGGUCUGAAGAAAGAAGAGGAAAGACAGAGGAAGGUGGAAGUUUUGAUCAGUAUAGCACAUGGUGUUUUUAAGUUGUUAAACCACGUUCAGGUUUCCACUUAAGUCAUGGGAAUAAAAGUGGACAAGGACUGAAGCUUUAUGAGCUCAGA